CGGAGGCUCCCCGGUAGGGACGGCCUGAGGCCGAGGGCACCCUGAGGGCGGAAGAGGCAAAGCGCCUCGCCCGCCGGGGCCUCGGAGGUGACUAACUCCUAGAGGCUGCGGCGGAGGGGAGAAGCCUGGUGGUACAUUCCAUGGCCCAGUGCCUCGGCCACUGGAAAAUCCCACAGGGGUAUAUCGAGUAGGGGACCGCGGGCUCCGCGGCAGAAAUGACCGCCCUUCCAAGAUGGCGGCUCCCGUAGAGACACUCCCAAGGAGACAGCCAUGUUCCUUGCCUGAGAGUCACUGAAGGAAAUUGGAAAGCCCGCCUCUCCUUCGACGCACACGCGCACGCGCACGCACGCACCGGCGCGGUCAUCCAGCACAGUGAGCGGCCCCUGGGCACCACCAGAAAACAUUUGUGAGUGAACGUGGAGUGAUGACCAUGUGGACACUGUCUUUCCAGGGUUUCUUGGAGCCUCUGCAGAGUCUGGGGGCCAGGCUUCUUAGUGGAAACUGCAGGAUCUUCCUUCUGACCCCUGCUUGCCUCGCCCCAGCAGCUCCGGUUGAGUCCACAGAUGCCAGCUCAGCUUCCAGCUUGGGGAAGAGUGGGGUUGUCAGCAGGAGAGCCUGAGGGCUGAGGCCCAGCGUGAACAUGGCAGCUAAUGGGGACUCUCCCCCAUGGUCCCCGGCCCUGGCUGCAGAGGGACGUGGCAGCUCAUGUGAGGCUUCAGUGUCAUUUGAGGACGUGACUGUGGACUUCAGCAAGGAGGAGUGGCAGCACUUGGACCCUGCCCAGAGACGCCUGUACUGGGAUGUGACACUAGAGAACUACAGCCACCUGCUCUCAGUGGGGUACCAAAUUCCCAAGUCAGAGGCUGCCUUCAAGUUGGAGCAAGGAGAGGGGCCAUGGAUGCUGGAGGGGGAAGCCCCACAUCAGAGCUGUUCAGGUGAGGCUAUUGGGAAAAUGCAGCAACAGGGAAUUCCUGGAGGAAUUUUCUUCCACUGUGAGAGAUUUGAUCAACCCAUAGGAGAAGAUUCAUUAUGUUCUAUUUUAGAAGAACUGUGGCAAGAUAAUGACCAGCUAGAGCAACGUCAGGAAAACCAGAAUAACCUUUUAAGUCAUGUGAAAGUAUUGAUUAAGGAGAGGGGCUAUGAACAUAAAAACAUUGAAAAAAUAAUUCAUGUGACUACCAAGCUUGUUCCUUCAAUUAAAAGACUCCAUAACUGUGACACAAUUUUGAAGCAUACUUUAAACUCACAUAAUCAUAAUAGAAACAGUGCAACAAAGAACCUUGGCAAGAUUUUUGGAAAUGGUAACAAUUUCCCCCAUAGCCCUUCCUCUACUAAGAAUGAGAAUGCUAAAACAGGAGCAAAUUCCUGUGAACAUGACCACUAUGAAAAACAUCUCAGCCACAAACAAGCUCCCACCCACCAUCAGAAAAUUCAUCCUGAGGAGAAGCUUUAUGUGUGUACUGAAUGUGUAAUGGGCUUCACUCAGAAGUCACAUCUGUUUGAGCAUCAGAGAAUUCAUGCUGGAGAAAAGUCCCGUGAAUGUGACAAAAGCAACAAAGUCUUCCCCCAGAAACCCCAGGUUGAUGUACAUCCAAGUGUUUAUACAGGAGAAAAACCCUAUCUGUGUACUCAAUGUGGGAAAGUCUUUACCCUCAAAUCAAACCUCAUUACACAUCAAAAAAUUCAUACCGGGCAGAAACCCUACAAAUGCAGUGAAUGUGGAAAAGCCUUUUUCCAGAGAUCAGACCUCUUUAGACAUCUGAGAAUUCAUACAGGAGAAAAACCUUAUGAAUGCAGUGAAUGUGGAAAAGGCUUCUCCCAGAACUCAGACCUCAGUAUACAUCAGAAAACUCAUACCGGAGAGAAACACUAUGAAUGCAAUGAAUGUGGGAAGGCUUUCACAAGAAAAUCAGCACUCAGGAUGCAUCAGAGAAUCCACACGGGAGAGAAACCUUAUGUAUGCGCUGACUGUGGGAAGGCCUUCAUCCAGAAAUCACAUUUCAACACACAUCAGAGAAUUCAUACUGGAGAAAAGCCGUAUGAAUGCAGUGACUGUGGGAAAUCCUUCACUAAGAAGUCACAACUCCAUGUGCAUCAAAGAAUUCACACCGGAGAGAAACCCUAUAUAUGUACAGAAUGUGGAAAGGUCUUCACUCACAGGACAAACCUCACCACACAUCAGAAAACUCAUACUGGGGAAAAACCCUAUAUGUGUGCUGAAUGUGGAAAGGCUUUUACUGACCAGUCAAAUCUCAUUAAACACCAGAAAACUCACACUGGAGAGAAACCCUAUAAGUGCAAUGGCUGUGGAAAAGCCUUCAUAUGGAAGUCGCGCCUCAAAAUACAUCAGAAAUCUCAUAUUGGAGAGAGACACUAUGAAUGCAAGGACUGCGGGAAAGCCUUCAUCCAGAAAUCAACACUAAGCGUGCAUCAGAGAAUCCAUACAGGAGAGAAACCGUACGUUUGUCCUGAAUGCGGGAAGGCCUUUAUCCAGAAAUCGCACUUCAUUGCGCAUCAUAGAAUCCAUACUGGAGAGAAGCCUUAUGAAUGCAGCGACUGUGGGAAAUGCUUCACUAAGAAGUCACAACUCCGUGUGCAUCAGAAAAUCCACACAGGUGAGAAGCCCAAUAUAUGUGCUGAAUGUGGAAAGGCCUUCACUGACCGAUCAAAUCUCAUAACACAUCAGAAAAUCCACACUAGGGAGAAACCCUAUGAAUGUGGUGACUGCGGGAAAACCUUCACCUGGAAGUCACGCCUCAAUAUACAUCAGAAGUCUCAUACUGGAGAAAGACACUAUGAAUGUAGUAAAUGUGGGAAAGCUUUCAUCCAGAAAGCCACACUAAGUAUGCAUCAGAUAAUUCAUACAGGAAAGAAACCUUAUGCUUGUACAGAAUGUCAGAAGGCCUUUACUGACAGAUCGAAUCUCAUUAAACACCAGAAAAUGCAUAGUGGAGAAAAACGCUAUAAAGCCAGUGACUGAGAAAGUCUUCACCUGGAAAUCACAACUGGGUAUGCAUCAGGUAUCUAAUAGCAGGGAGGAGGAAGGCCUGUUGCUGCAAUCAUUGUACAGGGGGAAAUGGGUAUGAGAGACUGAGGCUUGAGUGAACUGAAGGCAAACAGAGCCAAGUAUCCUUCAGUCCACUGGAAAGACAAGUUCCUGCAUCACCACAGUGUAUAUGCAAUUCUAUGCAUAGGAAGAGCCUUUAGAGAAAGCAUUUGAGCGAAAGUCAUGUUUGGUGACAUGAUUCAUACAGACCUCUUGAGCUCCUGGAAAUAGUAGAAUUAAGACCUGAGGAGAUGACUCGUCAUCUCUUAUGCUUCACUUUUUGGAUAAAGAACUUUUUAAAUUCAGUACUGAUUGGUUCAGCAUAUCCUGGGACAUAAAAAUACUCACUACUGGGAAAAACUUUUUCAAAUUUCUAGGUUGAGGAGAAGAGUUUUCAUUGUCCAAACACUGGCAGGGCACUGACAUCAAGGCAGAAAACCUACUUGGGAAUGCAGAUAUCUGUUUUUGUGAUCAUUGGCACUUAAGACAUAGAAAAGAUUUCCAUGAAAAACUUUUUUCUUUUCCCUUGGGAAGUCCUCAUGGUAUAUAUAUUUUAAGUGCAAUGGAAUUUUUAAAUUUAAAGAUAUAACUUUAUGAAUUGAGAAAUUAGGCCUAGCUCUAGGCUAUGUUACAGAAAUAUAGUCAUUGAAUGAUACAGACAUAUAAAGGUAGUAGUUGUCUCAUUAUUAAUUCCCUGCUGGGAGAGCAGAUGAGUCAUACCCUAUAAGAAGUAUGCAUGCCUUCUAACCUAUGUCCCCAAAGCUGUCAUUUGCAUAAGCUGCAGGCCAUAGAUUCCUGAUUCCCUCAGUAACUGACCCUACGACAAUGGAACUGAUCCACGGCACUCUAGAUUUUCAGGCUAACCCACCAACACCCCUGCUUUCCUUGGGAUUUCCUGAAAAAGAAUGGUUGAAAAAUUGAGUUUCACUUCCUAAUAUUUUGUUUUUCUUCCUAUUUGGUUAAGGUAUAUUCAUUUCCUACAUGCACAUUAAGGGUAGUUUUGUGUAGACUGCUAUGUGAUAAAGUCAUGUUGCAUUGCAAUUAGUUAUUCUAAGACAUAAUUACAGUUUAUCAUAGUUGAAUAACUGGAAGACUUCUCAAGAAAGAGCACUGCUCUUUUUUAACACUGAUAUAUAGACACGUUCUCAUUUUCCCUUAAACAUUUUUUACAAUACUCAUAAAAAGGAACUUUCUUUCUAGCAUGCAAUUGUAUUUUUAUUUUAUUUUAAAAUCUUUUUAUUAAACUAUAAUGUAUACAGAAAAUGCAUAUAUCAUAAACAUACAGCUCAGUGCAUUCUCAAAAACUGAACAUACUCAGAUCAAGAAACAGAACAUGACCAGCACCCCAGAAGCCUUCCCCACUUUCCCUUCCAGGCAAGCCCCCAAGGGUAUACAUUAUCCUGGCUUCUCACAGCAUAGAUUCAUUUUGCCUGUUUUGUAUUUUAUAUAAAUUGAGUCAAUUAUAUAUCAUAUAAUUGAGCCAUAUACUCUUUAGCAUCUGUCUUCUGUCAUUCACAUUAUGUAUGUGAGAGUCAUCCAUAUGUUGCAUAUAGUUGUAGAUAAUUCAUUUUCAUUGUCAUGUUGUAUCCCAUUCUGUGAAUAUGCUGCAAUAUAAUUUAUCCAUUCUACUGUUUGUAGACAUUUGGGUUGUUUGCAGCUUGGGCUAUUAGGAAUUGUGUUGCUGUGUAUUGGUGAACAUAUGUAUGUAUUCCUGUUAGGUAUGUACCUAAGUGUAUCCAUAUGUUCAGCUAUAUGUUAUAAAACCAGUUUUCAAGUGGUUGUACCAAUGUACACUCCCACCAACCCAGUAUGCGAGUUCUAGUGCUCCACAUACUUGCCAACAUUUGGCAUUUUCCAUCUUUUUUACUAUAGCCAUUAGUGGUGGGCAUAUAGUGAUAUGUCAGUUUUAGUUUUCGGUUUUAUUUUCUUGUCCUCCAAACCAUUGUAGUAUCUCCCCAGGAUAGAUGAGUGAUGGCUGAGACCUGAGACCUAGGCCUGUUCCUCACAUGACUGCACCAUUUUACAUUCUAUCAAUGUAUGAGGUUUCCGGUUUCUCCACAUCCUUACCAACUCUUAUUAUUAUUAGUCUUUUUUAUUAUAGCUAUCCUAGUACAUGUGAAGUUAUAUUGUGAUAUUAAUUUACACUGCCCUAAUGAUUAAUAAUAUUGAUCAUCUUUUAUUGAGAA